AUGUGCGUGUGUUUCUGCAGAGGAGGGGGCAUGGGCCCCUGCCGGGCUGCGCAGGGGAGGGUGGGGUGGGACUUUUCCAGAGAGGGAGCCAGGCCUGGCCCGGGCCCCGGGAGCUCACGUCACCCCCACCCCUCACUUCUCCAGGGAACUGCCAAAGCCAAACCCAGCUCGGGAUGGGAUUAUGUGUACUGGGUAGACCCGUGGAGAGGGGCUGCGAGAAGAGAUCUCGGUGGCAGAGAGAAGCAGAGGCAGAGAGGGCAUGAAGAGGGGUCGGCAUCAGAGAAGGGGCAGGCAGUGACUAUCACCCCAUUUCUUCUUCCCUCAGCUGGAGUAACAAGAGUCAGGCAGAGCCUGAAGACUUGGGUGGAACAUGGGCCCUUCUCUGGAGAUCCUGGCCUCCCCCGUUCAGUCAGGGUGGAGUUGCUGACCUUAGUGGCCGGCCCAGCCAGGGGAAGGAGUGGCCAUCGGCAACCCCCACCCCAACCCCAAUCCCUGAGGCGCCCGCUCUGGCUCAGCCACUCUGACCCCUCCCUCAAAUUCCGAACCCUAGGUCUCAGGGAGGGCAGUGGGGCUGAGUGUCUGCCCCCAGGCACAUUCCUACCCUUCUCUUGGUCAUUUUCUGCCCCAGAGCUGGCCCACCUCAGCAAUGCGAGGGCUCCCUGGAUUCCUCUCCCGGGUGCCUUUCAGAUCCAACAGAAACAGAUUUUUUUUUUCCUGGAAAGCAGAACUAAGAGUGGGAUGAGGAGCAGGGGUGGGAAGGACUCAAAGUGAGAAGAAGGGGGCAAAGAGAGUCAGGCUUGGUGGCUGGGGUGGCUUCCAAGCCUCACUUCUCCAGUGUUCAAAGCUGAACUUCAGAUGGACUUCCCGGCUCUUCAGAAUGAGAGGCCUGUGGCUGGGGCAUGAGGCAGCCCCGGCUGCACCUCUCCUUCCCGCUUCCCCAGCUGGUAGAGACGCACAGGAAACAAGCCCUCACUGAACCAACUCCAGAUGCUGGCACCCAGAGUGGGUGUUACAUUGCCGGCUUCUUCUCUAGAGAUUAAACCGUCAACCCAUUUAGCUUA